GUAUGUACUAAUGAAUGGGACUGCUGGCUCAGCGGCCCGCCUGGCUUUCCACUCUAUUAAAUUGUUUUCCAAAGUUAUACUGGUUUAUGCGCUCGCUCACCGCUCACCAGCAGGGUAGAAGAAUUCCUGAUGUUUGCACCCUGCCCAAAGCUGGUGGGUGUAGCGUGGUAUCCUAAGGUAGUUUUAGUUUGGAUUUCUCCAGACUUCUCUAACUUGAGGACCUUUUCAUAUUCACUGGCCGCUGUGAUUGUGCUUUUGUAAUGUACCUGCUCAAGUCUUUCACUCUUUUCUCAUUGCAAACGUACAUCCUAGGUUUCCAGCAGGAGAAACAGGCCUGUCCAUUUCUGACACAAGAUGGGUGAAUCGGUAACUUUUCUGGUCUGUUUUCCCACUGCUUGUUAUCCUUCUGUUUUCUUUAAUGGCUUUCUGCCUAGAUCAGGAGGGACAGACUUUCUUUUGAAACCCAAUAACACAACUGUUAUUUCAGUACAGAGCUAAGACAGAAAUAGCAGACAUAGUUCAAUGGUCCCUGCACCUAGAGAGUGCCGUGGAAACAGGGCCCAGUCACCCUCCAACUGCACAGUCCCAUGAAGCCAAAAAGACAAUCCAGGUUGGAGAAUGUCACCUUUCAUUUAAGGCCAAGUUUUGCAGAGUCUGUUUUAUUUGUUUUUAAGUCUGCUGCCUAACUUCUUUUGGGUUUUUGUGAACUUAGAGGACACAUAAUCUCACUCUUCUAGCAGUUUCUCUAGGAGGUGAUAACAAUGCGGACAAAUAAUUAGCCAUAAAACAUCUUGGCCAGGCGCAGUGGCCCACGUCUGUAAUCCCAGCACUUUGGGAGACCAAGGCAGGAGGAUCACUUGAACCUAGGAGUUCAAAACCAAUCUGGGCAACAUGGUGAAACCCCAUUGUUACAAAAAGUACAAAACUUAGCCAGGUGUGGUAGCAUGUGCCUGUAGUUCCAGCUACUCAGGAGGCUGAGGUGGGAGGAUCACUUGAGCCCAGGAGGUCAGGGCUGCAUUGAGCUGUGAUCCUGCCACUGGACUCCAGCAUGGGCAACAGAGUAAAACCCUGUCUCAAAAAAAAAAAAAAGAAAAAAAGCAAUCAAGUAUCUCCAGGGUAAAUGAAAGCAACAUGAAGAAUAAGCUGUUUAUAAAUACAUAUAAAUUAAAACUAAUGGAGAAAAACAGUAUACCACAUCACAGUCUAGUCUCAGCAAGGAAAACAACAGGCCAACAUUAGAAGACACGAAUGACAUAAAACAGAUCUUGAACAUUUUGUUAUUACUCAGAUCACGAAGGACUAGAUCACGCUGCACUCAGGGCUUAAAAAUCACAAGCCACGUUACACAUACAGUACUUCAGACAUUCUUCAUUCCUGACCGAGGUUUUUUUUGUUUUUGAGACAGAGUCUCACUCUGUCACCCAGUCUGGAGUGCAAUGUCGCAAUCUCAGCUCACUGCAGCCACUGUCUCCCGGGUUCAAGCAAUUUUCUCCUGCCUUAGCCUCUCCAGUAGCUGGGAUUACAGGUGCCCCCCACCAAGCCCAGCUAAUUUUUGUGUUUCAGUAGAAAUGGAGUUUCAUCAUGUUGUCCUCUCGAACUCCUGACCUCAAGUGAUCCACCCGCCUCGCCCUUCCAAAGUGCUGAGAUUACAGGUAUCAGCCACUGUGCCUAGCCAGCACUCAAUAAUUUAAUUGGCAUACUGAACUCUGUUCCACCCGGAAGUCAGUGGACUUCACAUUUCUCUGACGUUUGAUCUUAAAUAAGAGCAGCAGACUAGGAGAGGUGAGAAAGUGCUGAUUAAGCCCGAAGGUAAAUAGGAGUUAAGCAAACAAGAGAAGAAGGAAGAGUGAUGCAGAUGGAGGGAACAGCACAUGUGAAGAUCUGUGGUCAGAGCCAGGGUGGUGGUUUAGGAACUCCUCGGACAGUGUGGCUAGAGCACAGGCAAAGGACGAAAUUGGGUGAGGAAGAGUCUAACCUGUCUCUGCAAGCUCUUGAGUCCCGCCAAGAUGAUAUUUUAAAACGUCUGUAUGAGUUGAAAGCUGCAGUUGAUGGCCUCUCCAAGAUGAUUCAAACACCAGAUGCAGACUUGGAUGUAACCAACAUAAUCCAAGCGGAUGAGCCCACGACUUUAACCACCAAUGCGCUGGACUUGAAUUCAGUGCUUGGGAAGGAUUACGGGGCGCUGAAAGACAUCGUGAUCAACGCAAACCCGGCCUCCCCUCCCCUCUCCCUGCUUGUGCUGCACAGGCUGCUCUGUGAGCACUUCAGGGUCCUGUCCACGGUGCACACGCACUCCUCGGUCAAGAGCGUGCCUGAAAACCUUCUCAAGUGCUUUGGAGAACAGAAUAAAAAACAGCCCCGCCAAGACUAUCAGCUGGGAUUCACUUUAAUUUGGAAGAAUGUGCCGAAGACGCAGAUGAAAUUCAGCAUCCAGACGAUGUGCCCCAUCGAAGGCGAAGGGAACAUUGCACGUUUCUUGUUCUCUCUGUUUGGCCAGAAGCAUAAUGCUGUCAACGCAACCCUUAUAGAUAGCUGGGUAGAUAUUGCGAUUUUUCAGUUAAAAGAGGGAAGCAGUAAAGAAAAAGCCGCUGUUUUCCGCUCCAUGAACUCUGCUCUUGGGAAGAGCCCUUGGCUCGCUGGGAAUGAACUCACCGUAGCAGACGUGGUGCUGUGGUCUGUACUCCAGCAGAUCGGAGGCUGCAGUGUGACAGUGCCAGCCAAUGUGCAGAGGUGGAUGAGGUCUUGUGAAAACCUGGCUCCUUUUAACACGGCCCUCAAGCUCCUUAAGUGAAUUGCCGUAACUGAUUUUAAAGGGUUUAGAUUUUAAGAAUGGUGCUCUUUCAUGCCUAUUAUCAGUAAGGGGACUUGUAUUAGAGUCAGAGUCUUUUUAUUUAGGCCAGUUGUCAAGUGUCAAUAAAAGCAUCAUGUAAUUUA